AGACAAGGCCUUGCUAGGCUGUAGUGCAGUGGUACAAUCAUAGCUCUCCGCAGCCUUGAAUUCCUGGGCUCAACCAGUCCUCCCACCUCAGCCUCCCAAGUAGCUAAGACUGCAGGUGUGUGCUACCAUUCUCAGCUAAUUUUUUAAGAAAGUUUUUGUAGAGAUGAGGUCCCAUUAUGUUGCCCAGGCUGGUUUCAAACUCCUGGACUCAGUCAGUCCUCCUGCUUCAGCCUCCUGAGUAGCUGGGACUACCGGCGGGUGCCCCCAUGCCCAGCUAAUUUUUUUUUCAUAGAGACAGGGUCUUGCUAUGUUGCCCAGGCUGACCUCAAACUCCAGGCCUUAAGUGAUCGAUUUUUUUUUUUUUUUUUAAAUAAUUGGAACCCCCUGCCCUGGGACCUGGCCUUGCAUAACCCUGCCUCCAUCAGCUGACCCCAGGCAGCCCUGGCAUGCCCUUGAGUUGUGGUGGACACGCUGUAUCUUUCCAUGGCAGCUGCCUUCCUGGCCGUGUGUGCUGAGGACACCACUCCUGUGGGCAGCUGUUCCUCAGGCCACCCAGCUGCUCCUGCAGGCAGUCAGCCACACUGUGCCCAAAGGGCAGGGAGGCCACCUCUGAACAGCAGGGGGCCCGAGGCCAGGACUAGGCAUUGUACACUCAUACAGGAAGGAAGUUCUGAUGUUUUAACAGGAAGAACAUGGGCUUCAACUUUUGUUACCACAACAAGACCCAAAUUAGAGCUAAAACUAUGAGAACGAGUGUCAGGACCCACGAUCAUGUCAUUGCUGGCAGCCCCAUGGUCAGCCCACUCUGCAUGAAUGCAAACCUCCUCGUACUUUCUCUGCCUCCUCCCCAUACCCAAAGCCCGAGUGGGGCUGGCUCUCUCUAGUGCAUUGUUCUCAGCCUUCUCCGGCCUGGGUUGCUGGCCAGCAUGCUGACACGCUGAGCUAGCUGCUUCCCAAAUUGAGUUAGCUGUUACUGAGCCAGUGGGUGGUGGAGCACAGUUCUUGUCACCUGCCACUGGUAAAUGAAUUUAAAACUCUUGCUGAAAGGAAAGAAAUAUGGGGCAGAUGCAGACAGCCUCCAGCUGCUACAAGCAAAUGUGGCUCCCUUCAAAACACCAACUAACCCACCCAGCCCUUGGAGUAUUUAUUUGCAGGCUCUGCAGCCAGUGGGAGGAGCGCCUGAGGGAAGAGGUCAUGGCAGAGCCAUUUGGGAAGUUCCUGCAGUGGGAAAGGGUUUAGCUUCUCUGUGUCAGCAUCAGAGGUGGAGGAUUAUUUUCAAGAGAUAAGAGCAUCUCAUUGGCAAAAGAGCACAUUACAACCCCAAUGCCUUGUAGCUCAUCCCUCCUAAUCUUAUCAUAUAGUAUGUGCAGGGAGGAUGUGUUGCUUUCUACACUGGUAACAAACGACCACAAACUUGAGGGCUUACAACAUUUACCAUUUCACAGGUUCUGUGGGUCAGGAAUCUGGGCAGGGCUGAGUUCCAGCAUCUCCCUGAGUUAUGAUUCAGUGUGGGUCAGGGUGGUGGUCUCAUCAGAGGCUCAACUGGGGAAAAGAUCUACUUCCAAGCUCCCCAACAUUGUUGGCAGAUUUCAUUUCCAUAGGCCCUUGCACAGUGUAACUGCUCACCUCUCCACAGCCAGCAAAGGGAGUCAGGGAGUCUUCUCCCUUGUCAGCUCAGAUGAAAUCUCCUAUAAUGUAACCUAAUCAGGGACCUAUUGCCUUUGCCACAUUCCCUUGUUUAGAAGCCAGUCACAGGUUCUACUCACAAAGGCAUUAACACCAGGAGGCAGAUCAUGGGGGCUCCCUUCGAAUUCUGCCUACUGCAUGGAGGAUAUAGCCUUAUCAGUAAUGUUUCAGAAGUGUUCCCAAGUGAAGGCCCAGCCUGUAAUAGAGAUUCACAAUGUUUUCUCUUUGAAGUGAAGCAGUUUUGUUCAUUUCCUCCCAUCUCAGAAUGACUUCAAAUCCUGACAUCCUCGACAGCCCAAUACUUUGCCACAACCUGAUUACAACUCUAGCUCUCUUAUUUACUGGCUAUAUGUUAUUGAGAAAAGGUUUGUCCUGGUUGUGGUCAAGACUGGAUGAUGUAACUGGCUCUCUAGGAAGCCUCACUUGGCCGUAACCUCAGGAAGGUUCUCUUUGACCCCAUCUCAUUUCGAAGCCACUUCUGAAGCCACUUGAGAAAAAUGAUGUGACAGUUCCUAUCAAAAAGGAUUCAGAAACAUAUACCAUCUGUGAAGAAAGUGGCCCUUUCUCCCGCUUGCAAAAUAGACAUUCUCAAAUUCCAAAAUGCCAGCCAAGACCCCAAUUUACCUGAAAGCAGCCAAUAACAAGAAAGGAAAGAAAUUUAAACUGAGGGACAUUCUGUCUCCUGAUAUGAUCAGUCCCCCGCUUGGAGACUUUCGCCACACCAUCCACAUUGGCAAAGAGGGCCAGCACGAUGUCUUUGGAGAUAUUUCCUUUCUUCAAGGGAACUACGAGCUUUUACCUGGAAACCAGGAGAAAGCACACCUGGGCCAGUUCCCUGGGCAUAAUGAGUUCUUCCGGGCCAACAGCACCUCGGACUCUGUGUUCACAGAAACGCCCUCCCCGGUGCUCAAAAAUGCCAUCUCCCUCCCGACCAUUGGAGGAUCCCAAGCUCUCAUGUUGCCCUUAUUGUCACCAGUGACAUUUAAUUCCAAACAGGAGUCCUUCGGGCCAGCAAAGCUGCCCAGGCUUAGCUGCGAGCCCGUCAUGGAGGAAAAAGCUCAGGAGAAAAGCAGUCUGUUGGAGAAUGGGACAGUCCACCAGGGAGACACCUCGUGGGGCUCCAGCGGUUCUGCAUCUCAGUCCAGCCAAGGCAGAGACAGCCACUCCUCCAGCCUGUCCGAACAGUACCCCGACUGGCCAGCCGAGGACAUGUUUGACCAUCCCACCCCAUGCGAGCUCAUCAAGGGAAAGACUAAGUCAGAGGAGUCCCUCUCUGACCUUACAGGUUCCCUCCUCUCCCUGCAGCUUGAUCUUGGGCCCUCACUUUUGGAUGAGGUGCUGAAUGUAAUGGAUAAAAAUAAGUAACAAGAUGCCAACUUUUUUCCUUUGGGGUAAAAGGUACAAAAACAAACUAACCACAGUUGAAGAGAAGGGCUUCCGGAGCUGUAUUUGCAGUUUUGUGUUGGGUUUUCUAAAAUAAUAUUCUUACAAAGUAUUUUUUUACCUGUUAUGCCCUGUUUGCAAAAACAAUUUAGAAAAAAACAACAAAGCAAAACCUAUCUUGGCAAAAAAAGGAAGUGAGUCAGAGCCCAUUUUCAGGAGGCAUUGGUGAUGUUCGGCUCACAUAUUGUUUGCAGACACACAAGAAAUCUGGCUUGGCCAGGAUUGGCACUAGCUAUGAAGGGCUGAGCGAGUCACAUUAAGGAACUUCACGGAACUUUAUAGCACUCCGACAUUUUCUGAGCAAGAGGAAGUCAAAAUUUAUUUAACACCUAAGCCUUUUUGUAGACUCUUUUCUAUAUAUUGCUUAGGCUCACCAUAGCGAAUUCUCCAGUGUUAAAACUUUUCUGUUUUCACAUUUGAACUUUAUGGGUUUUGGGGAUUUUCUUGUAGUUCUUAUAUAUCCCUAUAUAUUAUAUCUAUAUUGCAAAAUUUUGACUGUCAGCUACAUGUUGGUAAGACACAGGCAAAGUAUUACUGUAACUAAGUUAUUUUUAAAGUUAAAAUAUAUUUUUACGUGCCUUUGGCUUUUUAUUGCAGAGUCUACAUUUUAUAGAUUCUACAUCAGAUGUUGUCACUUAUUUCCAUUGGGAUUCCAUUGUAAGCUGUGUAUGUGCGUGUUUGGAAAAGUGUAUUCAUACUUAGUUUUUUUUUCUUCAUCUGUUAUCAUACUUUUAACAGCAACCAAUAACGGAUUGUAAAGUGUAAAGGCACAGGUUACUCAUGAUGCUUCUGCAGAGACUGUGGGCUACACCACAUAUGUUAUUUGGAAAUAUAGGUAUUUUAGUACAGUACAUACUUGCAUUACAUAGGUACUUCAAGCAACACAAUAAAAAGUAAAUGAUAAAGUGAACUUGCUUGUUUAUAGUAAUAAACAAGACCAUAAGAGAAUAAGUAUAGCUAGAGAAAUUGCUUCUCUGAAAUGUACAUGAGCCCUUAAGGUAAGAGAUGAUUUCCAUCUACUCUCAUUUUGAUUACUUCCUUAUGGUUUGAGAGGCUAGAAACUGAGCCUCUCUACUUUUGGAAAAAUGAACAUGUGAGGUCAGAUUUUUUUUUUUUUUUUUAAGUCAGCACUGAUGCCACCCUCUCAGUGGUCAUUUCUGAGCAUCUUCCUGACUUGAACACCUUCUACAGCAAACUCUUGCAAGUCCAGUUUCAUCCCUGUAAGGCAAAUGUCUUUUCACGCAGAAAGUGCCAUAUAGACGAGAUAAAGGCAGCUAAAACGAGGGCAGUAGAGAGCACUUACCCGACCCCAAGGUGCCAGAGAUGCCCUGAGGAUGGUGGUUAAGGAAACAGGAGCAGGAAAUGUACACACAGAUUCCUGUCCCUUUGCCAACUACUCCUUCCCCAUCAAAGAAAAACACUUGCACACAGUAACUACCAGCUCCUUCUCUCAAACUUGUAUUUCUCCUGGAAAUGUAUCUCAGAAAUGACCUCCUCUCCCAACCACUUCAACGAUUCUUUCUUUGGGUUUGGGGUUCUUGCAGUUCUAUCAUCUAAAAUAACCUUUGGACUGCAGGUAAAAUGCAAUUAGGACAACUAACCAAGUAGACGAAACAAGUUCCCCUAGGCAGGGGUGUCCAAUAUUUUAGCUUCCCUGGACCGCAUUGGAAGAAUUUUCUUGGGCCACAUGUAAAACACACUAACACUAACCAUAGUUGAUGAGCUUAAAAAAAUAAAAAUAGAAAAUUGCAAAAAAAAAAAAAAAAAAAAAUCUCAGACUGUUUUAAGAAAGUUUAAAAAUUUGUGUUGGACUUCAUGCGGGCCACAGGUUGGACAAGCUUGCCCUAGGGCAUUGUGUGCUUUCCGUAACUUCUCAGUUGUAUUUCGUUAUCCAUGACUCUCCAGUGUUUUUUCUGUUGGACCACACCCGUCACAGUUCACAGUUCCAAAGAGAAAUUUCCCAGCCUAUUCUAAAUCUUGUUAAUGACGAAGAGUCCAAUGUAUCUCAUUAUUUGUAGCCAAUUUUAGACUCUUUUCAAUACCUCCCCCCCAUUUUAAUUAGUAUUGAUCAUAUUCAGUCUUUCAUUUUACUCUUCAUCUGUAGCGUGACCUCAAGGUAAAGAUGAAACUAUUUCAUGAAAAGGGGAGGAGUAUGGCUGUGCAUUAGCUCUACUCCCUCUCUGGUAAGUACUGGGGAGAGAACAGCCCUGCCAGUACUGGGUUUGAUAGAUUCUAAAUAUUAAUCACACAUCCUGCCUACAGUUAGCCAUUUUAGUUUCUGGGAGUUCUUUCAUGUACAUUUUCUUCCAUUAAUUGAAUUAGGUAUAAUUGAGAUGGCAAUAAAUAUGCCCGUAUUAGAAAGAGGAAACAAAGCUACAUGCGGCUUAUGAUUUUGUUGAGUCACUUCUCCCGAGGCAGCCUUUCCAAUGCCUGGUCCCUUCCCCUGAGAGCAGGUGGACUGCUGGUGGUGGCUUUCUUUCCUGCAGAGAGGCACUUUAGACCCAUACCUGCUGUGAGCUGAAUUGAUGUUCUCAUCCUGUGAACCUUCUCCCACUUUAACCUAAUUUAUCUUUACUUGUUUAAAGAUAAGGAAACCCAAGAUGUACUUUAUUUGCAAACUCAAAGCAAAUGGCGAGCCACCUGUGACCCAGUAACCAGAAAAGAAACCAUGCCAUUUGUAUAAGUAGAGACACUUCUUGUUGAGGUAGGCAAGGCUCUUGUGAGCGAUUUUUUUCCCCUAGUGAGACCUAACAAAAGACAAGCUAUAUCAUUUCUGCCUGAAAUUAUCUGCUUGAAAAGAUCAAAAUAUCAGGAUACUUAGCUCUUCACAAAUAUGAAGUCAUUAUCACAUUUCACUGAGCCAGAAAUCACUGUUAACAGCACACACAAAAGACUACACUGGUUGAACAGCAAAGAGAAACCCGGGUCUCCAGAAUCACAGUUUAGUCCUUCUAUAUUACUGCAAGUGACCUGUUUUUUCUGAAGGCUCCCCGCAAAUGAAGUCCUGGAAUGGAAAAAAUCCAUAAGUCCAUAAAUUAACUUGAUAAAUAUUUUAGAACAGACAAAAGAAAAUAUUGAGUGAUGUAGUUCUAAUCCUCCUAAUAUGGAACCUGGCAAGACUGAAUCAUUUUACUGUGAAAUAUAUAAACACAAUAGAAUGAGCCAACAUGAUGGUUUCUCUCCAGUAAGAGUUUUUCUUUUGGAAAUGAGGUUAACCUAGCCCCAAAUCUAGCAAUUCUCAUAAAAUCCGAUUUUAGAAUUAGCCUCCCAGAUUAAUCUGAAUGAUUGACUUAUUUUUUCUUAGGCAAGUCAGUAAGCCACCCACUAGACAGCCAUAUCCAGCAAAAUAAGAGAAGUUUCCAGAUGCCAAAUGAUAAGCCACCAUCAACCCAGCGGGGAAGCCUUCUGGUUGGUUUGGCUGUAUGAGAUUCAGGAAGGCCAGAAUACCCAAAAUUAUUCACACGACGUUAACUUAUUGGUACUGGCUAAGCAAUACAUGUAUUUCCUAAAGGAGGAGAUGGUCUUUUGGUUGAUUUAUGGACACACUUGUUUCAUCUGACUGUAAAUAUAUUGCAUGCUUUAUUCUGAUGGUGCACUAUUUCAUCCAGCAAGCUUUUCAUCUGAGAAUGUUUAAUGUUGACCUUAUUCUUAGAGCAAGUAGAUCUAAAUAUUUUUCAGCUGAGUUAUUAGGGAGUCAUUAUUCUGUGGUACAAUGCUGCAAAAAGCAUCAUGUGGAAGAAUGGGAACUAUGCUUACUUUAUGAAGUGAUGUAUAACACAAUGAAAUCUGUUUUACAACUAC